GCUCAGUCCUUUGGAUAUUAAUCUGACUGGGUUGGCUGGUGCACCUAAAUAAUACAUAUAUCCUCCUCAACCCCAUCGGUCUCUCUGAUUCCUAAAUCAUCCCCAAACAUUUCUGGUGGCCCAUAUGGGGAUUGGAGAUAACAGAUUUACUGUCUCCUUUGCCCAUGGGACUAGGGCCCUGGGGCUGUGGAAGACCUGGCAUCCAAGGCAUGCCAUGGGGGAGUUUCACCCGGAUGGAGACUGGCUCUCCCCGCAUCCUGCCCAGCAGUGCAACUGAACCUGAGAUGGGGCUGCAGGAUGACACCAGCACUUCAGGAACCGCGUUGCAGGUGUCACACCUUGGAUUCACCAUAGCUGGCUGAAACUAGCAGCAGCAGUGACUCCCGACUAUGACCAGUGGAUUAACCAACAAGACCCUGAUUGCCCCACCCGAAUAGACCUACGGCGAAUCCCAACCACCAGUAAGAAGGACAACUGCCCUGCUCUGACCACACUGGAGGCUGGUCAGUCUACACAUGGCUGAAGCUUGAAGAUCUUGCAAGCUCUGCUCUAGUCACAUCCUGGAAGCUGACUAGUCUACACACAGCCGAAGCUAAGAGGACCAUCUCUAGAUAAAUCCGCCUCUGAAGAGCACAGCUGUGUGGAAACAGGAAGUCAAGAACCAGUGGCCAUUUAUUUCACCAGUGGGACGACAGGCUCUCCUAAGAUGGCCCAGCACUCUCAGAGCAGCUUCAGCAUUGGGUUCACCGUCUGUGGAAGGACAGUCCAGAGAAAACUGCUGCCACGGUAAGGGGAGAUUUUUAUGUCACUGGAGACAGAGGAAUGAUGGACAGUGAUGGGUAUUUCUGGUUUGUCGGCAGAGCUGAUGAUGUCAUUAUUUCCUCUGGGUUUGUAGAUUUGCCACUCUUAAGAGGCAAGGAUUGACAGGGGGGGAGCUCUCCUACUGGAGGAUGUGGUGGUCAAAGGCUUCUUUUCCUUUUCAGGUACCGUAUUGGGCCAUUUGAAGUGGAGAGUGUGCUUGCUGAGCAUCCAGCAGUUGUCAAAUCAGCUGUUGUCAGUAGUCCAUAUCCAAUUUGUGGAGAGGUAGAUGAAUAUCAUUAAUUAAAGUAGCAACUUUAUAUUUUUGAGUUCUGUCCAUUUGACCAUGGUAAAGGCUGAACCAAAAGUGGUCAUUUAAUUCUCACUAUGAGGCAUGCAUUUGGCCAAAAUAUAAACCAGGCAACCAACUUUACAAUAAGUCGUGUCCCAAAGGGGAGCUAUUAGGAUUCUUUUGAAGGCAAGUGACAGAAACUCAACUCAAACUGCCUUAAGUUAAAAAAAAAAAAAAGACAUUUGGCUCAUAUAAAUGACAAGUAUUCAAGUACAGCCACAUCCAAGGGUUCAUGUAAGGUUGGCAAGUCUUAGUCUCUCUCCAUUUUUGGCUCUGCUGUUCUUUAUGCUGGCUCCAUUUGAGCAGGUUCUUCCUAUUUGAUAGCAAUCAACUCCAGACUUACACAGGUUAACAAUCCUCCACCCCUCCAGGAAAGGACAGAGCUCUCUUUUCAGUCAUUUCAAGUAACUCUCAGGACUGCAUUUGCCUACCUUAGAUCACAUCUCUCACCAAUGUGGUUCAGGGAAUGAUAUAUGCUGAUCGGCCAGACUUGGAUCAUAUGUCUAUCAUUGGAGGUAGGGGUUGGUGUCAAUCCCACCAGAGAGGAUAGGGUAAUACUCUAUAGGAAAAACUACAGUAGCUACUAAAAAGGGGGAACAGAUACUGCAUAAGCAUAUGCAGAUUUCACUGAAUAGGCAGCAGAUUUCACUGAAUGGACAACUGUCAUGGAACUCAGAAUACAUUUUCUCACAGAAACAAGGCAGAUAGAAAAUUGUGGCCAGUUUCCCAAACAAGUCUCAUGAGCCUGUUUAGGACCAAUGGGAAGGAAACUCUGGCAAUGACAAUAAUAGUCUUAAUUCUAGGAAGAAGCCCAAUUUUCCUAAUUUCCUUUCCUCAUGGAAGUUUCCUACAGACACAGCAAGUGACAAAAUUUCAAAAGUUUGUCUCUCAGCAUCCUCCCACAUCUGUACCUCCCUCUCACACACCAGUGAGCCUCUGCAGUGACACUAUGGGUCCCCUACUCUUACCUCUUAUACCCCCUCCACUCCCAUUUAUUCCAUUCUCAGAAAUAGUUUCCUCCUGCUGCCAUGUUCUCAUCCUCUCAAUAUAAAUGAUUUCAGCUGAAGAGCAGAAGUAACCACCAAUUAGAAUCAAUGAAUAAUAUAAAUUAUGCUUACUAACCUCAGUAAUUAUCUAAUUGGUAGGUUUUAAACAGUAUUACAAAGAGAAGCAAACAAUAUGAGGCAAAAAACGACCUUAUAGAGAUAGAUCAAUCUUUCCUGAGAGUUUUUUGUUUCAUUUUGUUUUGUUUUGAGAUGGAGACUUGCUGUCACCCAGGCAAAAAGCAGGAGUGCAGUGGUGCAGUUAUAGCUCACUGCAACCUCAAACUGCUGGGUUCAAGCAUCCUCCCGCCUCAGCCUCCUGAGUCGCUAGGACUACACAUGUGCAUUAUCGUGCCCUGGCUAAUUUUUUCUUUUUAGUCUUUAUAGAGAUGGGGUCUCACUAUGUUGACCAGGCUGGUUUCAAACUCCUGAGCUUAAACUAUCCUUCUACCUUGGCCUCCCAAUGUUGUGGGAUUAUAGGUGUAAGCCACUACACUCAGCCCCUUCCUGAGAUUUGAUCUCCCAGGAUACACAGUCCUUCCUCCAUUGAGACUCUUCAAACUCCCUUGAAACCACAUAUUCUCUGGGAGCUCCAUUUGUCCCCCUGGUACAUGCUUCUAGUGGUAUAGAUUCGAAGGAGUAAGUGGUCAUCUAUAAAGCAAAGACUGCCUGUGAAAUAAAUGGGAUCACUCUGAAAUGUUAAAUACAUGUGUGACCUGUAAAUAGAACUUAGCUUUCUUGAACCGCUGCACUCCUCAUACUCACAAACCAUUUACCUGGAAUUAUUCUCAAAACCUCACUUUGUAAUUGUAUCCAAGCUUUGUUCAGAAGCAAUCUCUGGCAUUUGCAGUCAUCACUCAAACUGCUAUUAACAAACAGUAAGUACCUAUGUUCAGCAUUGGUUGCAGAUCCUUGAUGUGUCUGAAAAACAGAGCAAGAUAAAUUAUCUGUUGCAGGUGGUGAAAGCUUUUGUUGUCUUAGCUCCAUCCUGUAAGUCCUACAGCCUAGAGAAAUUAACUCUUGAGCUUCAGGAUCAUGUGAAAAAAAUCAACUGCACCUUACAAAUAUCCAAGAAACCCAAAGAUAAGAAUGAAGAGACACUAAACCUCUGAUUUUUGCAUUCUAAAGAGAAUUGUCAACAAGGACUAAGUGAAGCAUCUCUCUCCAGGUUUGUGAAAAGGUGUCAGAGCCAGAGGAGAAGAGUGGACAACCCAACUGCCCACCACAGGUCCCUAGAAGUACAGGUCAAGCCUAUGCUGGGGAGAGGCAAACAGUUUCCUGGUACAUAGCCGCUAAAACCCCUGGAAUUUCUGAAGUGAUGAACUGGUCUCUGUGCAAAUCCUGAGUGCUAAAGCUUCCAACAAGACUGAUGCUAGCUCGUGUCACCAGGAAGAUGCUACGUCAUGCCAAGUGUUUUCAGCGCCUAGCAAUUUUUGGUUCUGUGAGGGCACUGCAUAAAGAUAAUAGAACAGCAACCCCUCAGAAUUUCUCCAACUAUGAAUCCAUGAAACAGGACUUCAAACUGGGGAUUCCAGAGUAUUUCAACUUUGCUAAAGAUGUCCUGGACCAAUGGACUGAUAAGGAAAAGGCUGGAAAGAAACCUUCAAAUCCAGCCUUCUGGUGGAUCAACAGAAAUGGAGAAGAGAUGCGAUGGAGUUUUGAGGAACUGGGAUCUCUGUCCAGAAAAUUUGCCAAUAUACUUUCAGAAGCCUGUUCCCUACAAAGAGGAGAUCGGGUAAUUCUGAUUCUGCCCAGGGUCCCAGAGUGGUGGCUUGCAAAUGUGGCCUGUCUGCGAACAGGGACAGUUUUAAUUCCAGGAACCACUCAGCUGACCCAGAAAGACAUUCUCUACAGACUACAAUCUUCAAAAGCAAACUGCAUUAUCACCAAUGAUGUUUUAGCCCCAGCAGUAGACGCUGUUGCAUCCAAAUGUGAAAAUCUGCACUCCAAGCUGAUUGUAUCAGAGAACUCCAGAGAGGGGUGGGGGAACCUCAAGGAGUUGAUGAAAGUCUUUCUCUGUCACCCAGGCUGGAGUACGGUGGCUCGAUCUUGGCUCACUGCAACCUCCACCUCCCUGGUUCAAGCGAUUCUCAGCCUCCUGAGUAGCUGGGAUUACAGACAUGCCAGUGACAGCCACACCUGUGUGAAGACAAAACACAAUGAGAUCAUGGCCAUAUUCUUUACCAGUGGAACAAGUGGAUAUCCGAAAAUGACUGCACACACCCACAGCAGUUUUGGUUUAGGAUUAUCUGUAAAUGGAAGGUUCUGGCUAGAUUUGACACCCUCAGAUGUGAUGUGGAAUACCUCAGAUACGGGCUGGGCAAAGUCUGCAUGGAGUAGUGUUUUUUCUCCGUGGAUCCAGGGAGCAUGUGUAUUCACACACCAUUUACCCCGUUUUGAGCCGACUUCUAUCUUGCAAACACUCUCCAAGUACCCCAUCACAGUCUUCUGUUCAGCACCAACUGUAUACCGAAUGCUUGUACAGAAUGAUAUAACCAGCUAUAAGUUUAAAAGCUUAAAGCACUGUGUGAGUGCUGGGGAACCAAUUACCCCUGACGUGACUGAAAAAUGGAGAAACAAGACGGGCCUGGAUAUCUACGAAGGAUAUGGACAGACUGAAACGGUGCUAAUCUGUGGAAAUUUUAAGGGAAUGAAAAUUAAACCUGGCUCAAUGGGAAAACCUUCUCCUGCUUUCGAUGUUAAGAUUGUAGAUGUAAAUGGCAAUGUUCUACCUCCUGGACAAGAAGGAGAUAUUGGCAUUCAAGUUCUACCCAACCGACCAUUUGGCCUUUUUACUCAUUACGUAGAUAAUCCUUCAAAAACAGCUUCAACUCUACGAGGCAAUUUCUAUAUCACUGGGGACAGAGGAUAUAUGGAUAAAGAUGGGUAUUUCUGGUUUGUUGCAAGAGCAGAUGAUGUCAUAUUAUCCUCUGGCUAUCGAAUUGGACCAUUUGAGGUAGAAAAUGCCCUGAAUGAACACCCUUCAGUUGCAGAGUCAGCUGUUGUCAGCAGCCCAGACCCCAUCAGAGGAGAGGUAGUAAAGGCUUUUGUCGUUCUAAAUCCUGAUUACAAGUCACAUGAUCAAGAACAACUAAUAAAGGAGAUUCAGGAGCAUGUUAAAAAAACUACAGCACCUUACAAAUAUCCCAGAAAGGUAGAAUUUAUUCAAGAGCUGCCAAAGACUAUCAGUGGGAAGACAAAAAGAAAUGAACUGAGGAAGAAAGAAUGGAAGACAAUUUAAAGUUGUUUCAUUAAUUACCAUAUCUAUAAAACAAACAUAGUAUCUGUCAAUCUCUAGAAACCACAAGAUGAUGGAGAGGUCAUAAAAACUGUGGUAGUAUGCUUAGAAACUGUUGAUUUAAAAUAUCUUGUGGUUAUGAUAUCAGAGGCUAAAUUUUGAAAUAAAAUAUUUGGCAAAUUCCUCCACAUUAGUGUCAAUGUUCCUAUCAUUUCUUAAUAUAAAAAUAAUACCAUCAAUUGCUGAUUAAUUUUUAAAUGUAUAGUAUAGAAGCAGUUUCUGAACCAGAUCUCUGCUACAUAGGUUUUCAAACUUUAGUUGACUAAUUCUUCUGAUAUGUUGAUAUACAAAUCAGAACCAAUGUUCAAGCCUGAAAUAAAACUAAAGAACUUAUAAAAGUUUUUAGAAAAAUAUAAAAUAUCAGUUAGAAGAUUAUGAUAAUCUCAAAGUACAAGAAUCUACCUGAAAAUAGACUAGGGAUUUUUAUUAGUCACAUUUUUUGCAAAUAAUUUAAAAAUAGUUUAGACUUGUUUCAAGGUCUAACUAUAAAAGAAGGAUCAUAUACUAUUGUUGCUUAUUAUAUGUAAUCUAAUAAAUACUGUUUACAAAAGA